GUAUUUUUAGUAGAGAUGGGGUUUCACCAUGUUGGCCAGGCUAGUCUCGAAUUCCUGACUUCAGGCGAUCCACCUGCCUUGGCCUCCGAAAGUGCUUGGAUUUCAGGAGUGGCCACCGCGCUCGGCCCUAAAUUCUUUUAUUUAACUUUUAAGUUCAGGGUUAUAAGUGCAGGUUUGUUAUAAAGGUAAACCUGUGUCUUGGGGGAUUAUUGUACAGAUUAUUUCGUUUUCAAAGAGAAUUUGCAAGUAUGUCACAAAAGCCUCAUAAACACGUUGUGAGAUUUUAAGAGGCAAUGACCGAGGCUUGGAGAUGUCUCGUCCUGUCCAAUGUCACCGCUAGACCUGAGAAUCUGCACUUGGGAGCUUACAGACCCGGUUCUCAGGCUUCACUUGAGACCCCAAGAAAGAAAAAAACCCACCAGCCAAAGAGGAGGAUGGCAGCCUGGAAGAACCUAAGGAAGCGAGGCUCAGAGUGGGGACACCGGACCGAGUGCACACUGGAGGUCCCAGAGCACGACGAGCGCGGAGGACCGGGAGGCUCCCGGGCUUGCGUGGAUGCAAGAGACAGGCUGGCUGUCCUGGCGGGAAGGAGCAGAAUAUCUGAAAGCUUCAACCAUGAGGUCCAGACACACGAGGCCUGCGUGAGACUCAGGACAAUGGAAAACUGCCCCCAGUGCCACCACCAUCGGACAAGCAGGCAGCAAGCAGGCAUCACGUGCCCUCCCCCCAUGUCCGUGGAACACGCAGACAUCUGGGUCAAGAGCUACAGCUUGUACUCCAGGGAGCGGUACAUUUGUAACUCUGGUUUCAAGCGUAAAGCCGGCACGUCCAGCCUGACGGAGUGCGUGUUGAACAAGGCCACGAAUGUCGCCCACUGGACAACCCCCAGUCUCAAAUGCAUUAGAGACCCUGCCCUGGUUCACCAAAGGCCAGCGCCACCCUCCACAGUAACGACGGCAGGGGUGACCCCACAGCCAGAGAGCCUCUCCCCUUCUGGAAAAGAGCCCGCAGCUUCAUCUCCCAGCUCAAACAACACAGCGGCCACAACAGCAGCUAUUGUCCCGGGCUCCCAGCUGAUGCCUUCAAAAUCACCUUCCACAGGAACCACAGAGAUAAGCAGUCAUGAGUCCUCCCACGGCACCCCCUCUCAGACAACAGCCAAGAACUGGGAACUCACAGCAUCCGCCUCCCACCAGCCGCCAGGUGUGUAUCCACAGGGCCACAGCGACACCACUGUGGCUAUCUCCACGUCCACUGUCCUGCUGUGUGGGCUGAGCGCUGUGUCUCUCCUGGCAUGCUACCUCAAGUCAAGGGCCUCUGUCUGCUCCUGCCAUCCCCGCAGUGCUGGACAUACAUGCUCAGUGGGAAGCGUCUGUUGAUUUGAGGGCAACCCCCUCCUCUUUUCAAAACCUAUGAACCACCUGCUUUGCAGGCAAACUCCCCCGCUGGCCAGCGUUGAAAUGGAAGCCAUGGAGGCUCUGCCGGUGACUUGGGGGACCAGCAGCAGAGAUGAAGACUUGGAAAACUGCUCUCACCACCUAUGAAACUCGGGGAAACCAGCCCAGCUAAGUCCGGAGUGAAGGAGCCUCUCUGCUUUAGCUAAAGACGACUGAGAAGAGGUGCAAGGAAGCGGGCUCCAGGAGCAAGCUCACCAGGCCUCUCAGAAGUCCCAGCAGGAUCUCACGGACUGCCGGGUCGGCGCCUCCUGCGCGAGGGAGCAGGUUCUCCGCAUUCCCAUGGGCACCACCUGCCUGCCUGUCGUGCCUUGGACCCAGGGCCCAGCUUCCCAGGAGAGACCAAAGGCUUCUGAGCAGGAUUUUUAUUUCAUUACAGUGUGAGCUGCCUGGAAUACAUGUGGUAAUGAAAUAAAAACCCUGCCCCGAAUCUUCCGUCCCUCAUCCUAACUUUCAGUUCACAGAGAAAAGUGACAUACCCAAAGCUCUCUGUCAAUUACAAGGCUUCUCCUGGCGUGGGAGACGUCUACAGGGAAGACACCAGCGUUUGGGCUUCUAACCACCCUGUCUCCAGCUGCUCUGCACACAUGGACAGGGACCUGGGAAAGGUGGGAGAGAUGCUGAGCCCAGCGAAUCCUCUCCAUUGAAGGAUUCAGGAAGAAGAAAACUCAACUCAGUGCCAUUUUACGAAUAUAUGCGUUUAUAUUUAUACUUCCUUGUCUAUUAUAUCUAUACAUUAUAUAUUAUUUGUAUUUUGACAUUGUACCUUGUAUAAACAAAAUAAAACAUCUAUUUUCAAUAUUUUUAAAAUGCA